AGUUUUGCUCCGAAAGACUUACCGAGGAGGGAGCUUGCGGUGCGUUCUGGGAAAGUUGCUGGGCCAGCUCCUUUGUUUCCAGUCUGAGCGUUGCGUUCGGUUUCCCGAGGGUCUUCUGAGGCACCGCGGCUGCGGGCUUCUGAGUUCCCGGCUCUCCGCAGGGAAGCCUCCUCUUCGUACCUCGUUUUUUGGCUCGUGGGGGGUCCUCCCACCGCUGGCCGACGCAGCCAGCAUGUCCGGGGUGCGCGCAGUGCGGAUCAGCAUCGAAUCGGCCUGCGAGAAGCAGGUCCAUGAGGUGGGCCUGGAUGGCACCGAGACGUACCUGCCCCCGCUGUCCAUGUCGCAGAAUCUGGCGCGUCUGGCCCAGCGGAUAGACUUCAGCCAGGGUUCGGGCUCCGAGGAGGAGGAGGCGGCGGGGACCGAGGGCGACGCGCAGGAGUGGCCGGGCGCCGGGUCCAGCGCAGACCAGGACGACGAGGAAGGAGUGGUAAAAUUUCAGCCUUCCCUUUGGCCUUGGGACUCAGUGAGGAACAAUUUGAGAAGUGCCCUGACAGAGAUGUGUGUUCUCUAUGAUGUUCUCAGUAUUGUUAGGGAUAAAAAAUUUAUGACUCUUGAUCCUGUCUCUCAGGAUGCACUUCCUCCAAAACAGAAUCCUCAGACGUUGCAAUUGAUAUCUAAAAAGAAGUCACUUGCUGGAGCAGCACAAAUCUUAUUGAAGGGGGCAGAAAGACUGACUAAAUCAGUUACCGAAAACCAAGAAAACAAGCUACAAAGAGACUUCAAUUCUGAGCUUUUGCGAUUACGGCAACACUGGAAACUUCGAAAAGUUGGAGAUAAAAUUCUCGGAGAUCUGAGCUACAGAAGUGCAGGAUCUCUCUUUCCUCAUCAUGGUACAUUUGAAGUAAUAAAGAAUACAGAUCUCGAUCUGGAUAAAAAGAUACCUGAAGAUUACUGUCCUCUUGAUGUCCAAAUUCCUAGUGAUUUAGAGGGGUCUGCAUAUAUCAAGGUUUCAAUACAAAAACAGGCUCCAGAUAUAGGUGACCUCGGCACAGUUAACCUCUUCAAACGACCUUUGCCCAAAUCCAAACCAGGUUCCCCACAUUGGCAGACAAAAUUAGAAGCGGCACAGAAUGUUCUCUUAUGUAAAGAAAUUUUUGCACAGCUCUCUCGGGAAGCUGUUCAAAUUAAAUCACAAGUCCCUCACAUUGUGGUGAAAAACCAGAUUAUCUCUCAGCCCUUUCCGAGCUUGCAGUUAUCUAUUUCUUUGUGCCAUUCCUCAAAUGAUAAGAAAUCCCAAAAAUUUGCUACUGAGAAGCAAUGUCCGGAGGACCACCUUUAUGUCCUAGAGCAUAAUUUGCAUCUACUGAUUAGAGAGUUUCAUAAACAGACCUUGAGUUCCAUCAUGAUGCCUCAUCCAGCAAGUGCACCUUUUGGCCACAAGAGAAUGAGACUUUCGGGUCCUCAAGCUUUUGAUAAAAAUGAAAUUAAUUCAUUACAGUCCAGUGAAGGGCUUCUGGAAAAAAUAAUUAAACAAGCAAAGCAUAUUUUUCUAAGGAGUAGAGCUGCUGCAACCAUUGACAGCUUAGCAAGCCGAAUUGAGGAUCCUCAGAUACAGGCUCAUUGGUCAAAUAUCAAUGAUGUUUAUGAAUCUAGUGUGAAAGUUUUAAUCACAUCACAAGGCUAUGAACAAAUAUGCAAGUCCAUUCAACUGCAAUUGAAUAUUGGAGUUGAGCAGAUUCGAGUUGUACAUAGAGAUGGAAGAGUAAUUACACUGUCUUAUCAGGAGCAGGAGCUACAGGAUUUUCUUCUGUCUCAGAUGUCACAGCACCAGGUACAUGCAGUUCAGCAACUCGCCAAGGUUAUGGGCUGGCAAGUACUGAGCUUCAGUAAUCAUGUGGGACUUGGACCUAUAGAGAGCAUUGGUAAUGCAUCUGCCAUCACGGUGGCCUCCCCAAGUGGUGACUAUGCUAUUUCAGUUCGUAAUGGACCUGAAAGUGGCAGCAAGAUUAUGGUUCAGUUUCCUCGUAACCAAUGUAAAGACCUUCCAAAAAGUGAUGUUUUACAAGAUAACAAAUGGAGUCAUCUUCGUGGGCCAUUCAAAGAAGUUCAGUGGAAUAAAAUGGAAGGUCGAAAUUUUGUUUAUAAAAUGGAGCUGCUUAUGUCUGCACUUAGCCCUUGUCUACUAUGAUUUUUUCCAGAUGUUUCCUAAAGAAGUUUCCAGAAACUUUGACUUGAAAUGUUUGCAGAUCAACUAUAAGCACAAAGAAGAGAUAACUUCCAAAAGAGUGCUGUUUUUAAAAAUAAUAAUUAGGAAAUGUUUAUUUAGCACUUUCAAACUUUUCACUUUAUAAAUGACAAGUGCUUUGAAAUGCAGAAGUUUAUGUACAGUUGUAUAUACAGUAUGACAAGAUGUAAAAUAAUAUGUUUUUCAUGCAGUUUAAAAUAUUACUAACUUAAGGGUUUCUAUGUGCUUUUUAAAAUAUUCCUUCUUUGAUGUUGACAUCAAAUAAAGUAUGUGGUUUAAAAAAAUCUCCAAAUACCUUUUUUUCCCCCCAAAUACUUUCUAAACUUUUUUUUUUUGAGAUGGUAUCUCACUCUGUAGCCCAGUCUGGAGUGCAGUGGUGUGAUCAUGGUUCACUGCAGUCUUGACCUCCCAGGCUUAGGUGAUCCUUCUGUCUCAGCCUUCCGAGUAGCUGGGACCACAGGCAUGCACAACCACGCCUGGCUAAUUUUUGUAUUUUUUAUAAAGACAGGGUUUUUCCAUGUUGCCCAGGCUGGUUUCGAACUCGGCUCAAGUGAUCUACCUGCCUCUGCCUCCCAAAGUGCUAGGAUUACAGGCGUGAGCCACCAUGCCCAGCCUACUCUAAAUUAUUGAUAACCUCUUCCUCCAGUUGUCUCCUUUAAGCUUUCCUGGGUCUAACCUACAUAGGUAAUUUAAGAACAUCCUCAGAAAGGACAGCUGAAGGCAAUAGGAGGCAGAUUAUCUCUUUAGGGCGUCCUCAAGUUUUUUUGGUCUGUUCUCCCACUUGAUUGACCUCACCAGUUGAGACACCUAGUGUAUGGCUCAUGCCCAGCCUUCCACCUGGGAUUCUCCAGCCUCCACCCAGCAGCCCUGGAUUGCUUUCUCCAAUUAAGGCCUUUCCAUCAGCUCUCUGCUUUUUCAAAGCGAAAAAACUAAUGGAUUAGUGGGUUAUCUUUUCCAAGGAACAGGUUUGCACUUCUUGGAAAAAGUGCCUAAAGUGUGCCCAUUAAUAUGAGGAUAGAUUUAGGCUCAUAAGCCUUUUGGUAACACUGAAAGUAGUAUCAUAUAGGCAAGCUCUCCUUAUAAGUAAGGCUUUCAAUUUUUAAAACAGACAUCCUGCUUUAACAAUUUGUAAGAUGACUGUGCAGUAAUAAAAGUCCUUUGUAUUUCUCCACCGUGUUUUCAUUAAAGAAAAAUGGAGCUUGUGGGCCACGAUAGAACAACUUUGUGCUUUUUUCCCCUUCUGAUCAAGAUCUUGCAUCUUUCUAUCCAUGGAAAUUAAAAUAAUUGGUAUGAAUUUGCAGUUAUUUAAAAAUCUUGAGUGCUUCAAAAAUUAUUGUUGCCUGCAAAAUUUGCCUUGGUCAAUAGGCUAAUCUGCACAAUUCCACUCACAUAAGGAGUCUUUUAUGUGAUUUUGAAGGCUCAGGCUAGAAGAGUGAGUCUGAGACUUUUGCUGAAUGACCAGUUUUUGUUUAUAUAAACUUCUCCCAUUGCAGAUUGAUACUUUGGUAAACUAAUAAAAAUGAAUUCCUAAAAUGAAAUUUUGAAAAGAUACAAAAUAAAAGCCCCAUUUAUUUGAUUAUAACUUGAUUAAAUUGCAUCAAAUACUAGAAUUUAUAGACAGAGUCUCACUCUGUUCCCCAGGCUGGAGUGCAGCAGCACUGUUUUGGCUCACUGCAACCUCUGCCUCCUGGGUUCAAAUGACUCUCAUGCCUCAGCCUCCCGAGUAACUGGGAUUACAGGUGUGUGCCACCACGACCGUCUAAUUUUUGUAAUUUUGAUAAGAGGGUUUUGCCAUCUUGGCCAGGCUGGUCUUGAACUCCUGGCCUCAAUUGAUCCGCCCACCUCGGCCUCCCAAAGUGCUAGGAUUACAGGCAUAAGCCACAGUGCCCAGCCCCCCCAAAUAUAAACAUUUCUGAAUGCUUUAUUUUUUAUUUCUCUGCUUGUCAUGAAUCAGUAACAAAUCAUGGACCAGGACCACACCUUGAGUAGAAUGGCUGAGAAUACAUGUGCAGAUACUACCGUCUGUUCUUUUAAACCCCAUCUGAGUAGAGUGGGAUAACUGAAGACUUUACGUUCUUCAUGUCUUACUUUCCCUGUUUGGUACGUCGCUGUAGUGAGUAGCCAGUACCGACCUAAAGAAUUGUAGAAACUAAAGCAAAUGUGUGGGAAAAUGGUAGCUUAGUUGCUGUGGUAGCAAUUCUUAUGCCUUGUAUUUAUUUACAUUUUCUAGUUUAAUGUUUUAACCUGAAUUUCCUGGAGUUUGAAGGAUGUGCUAUGGAAACUUGGGAGACAGUUUGAAGAAAACCAAUUAGCCCCUCAACAAGUAUUAACAGGUUGGCAAGGAGCUGUGUUUGAAUCUUGGCUCUGCUACUGGCUUGCUGUAUGAACUUGGCAAGGAUUCUCUGUGAACUUGUUUCCUUAUAUAUAAAUGAAGAUAGAGGUGCCUCCUCUACUAACCUCAGUGGUGAUUGAGAAGUUUCAGUAACGUUGGUAAUAAAUGUUAAAUUCUAAAGUACUACAUAAAUAUAAAGCAUUAAGCAAGUGUGCUUCUAAGAGUCAAGCCAAUUAGAAAAAAUGGUUGAGACACCAGCUGUAUUUAUUAGGAGAAAGCAUUUCAGAAUGUCCUGUAUUCAUAUUUGUAUGAUGUUUUAUAUAUGGUGAAGAUAUUGAGUGUUUUUCAUCAGAUUUCUUUGCUGGAACACCAUCAAAUCAAAGGGAUAACCUGAUUAUCUCAUGUUGAUCAGGAAUUGUAAUUGGCCCUUAAAUGCUGGGAUUACAGGUAUGAGCCACCAUGCCUGGCCUCCUUAGGUAUUGCUGAUGAAUAAAAACAGGGGCAACUACA